CAGCUCCCGCCGGGCGGCUGUGACGGCCGCAGCGGGUCGCAGAGCAGGGAGUGGACACGGAGUGGGGAGCGGAGAGGGAAGGAGGAGGAGGAGGAGCAAAGGUGUUGGAGAGAAAACUUCAGAAAGGAACAGGAAACCUGCCGGGGAGGCGGCGGCGGCUGCGGCUUCUCUGGGCGCCUGGGCUGCGCUCUUCGCGGGGUGUCCGCAGCUGCGGCUUGGCCCCGGUCUGGCUUCCCCGGCGCGCACGCACGGCUGAGCCGCGACGCUCAGUGGCUCGGGCCGUGCCCUCCGCCGCGGCUCUUGGCCGCUGUAGUCCCGCGAUCCGAUCCGCUUCUGCCGCGGCGGCUCCCUGGAGAGAGGGCGGCGAGGGCGCAGGGAAGAAGAGGGACGUCCACUGUGGAACAUGAAGCAGCAUGACUGAGAAAAUGUCCAGCUUCCUCUACAUAGGGGACAUCGUGUCCCUGUACGCGGAGGGCUCGGUCAACGGCUUCAUCAGCACCUUGGGGUUAGUGGAUGACAGAUGUGUGGUGCACCCAGAGGCCGGGGACCUUGCCAACCCUCCCAAGAAGUUCAGAGACUGCCUUUUCAAGGUGUGCCCUAUGAACAGAUAUUCUGCCCAGAAGCAAUAUUGGAAAGCAAAGCAAGCCAAACAAGGGAACCACACCGAGGCAGCCUUGCUGAAGAAACUACAGCACGCUGCAGAACUGGAACAAAAACAAAAUGAAUCGGAGAAUAAGAAACUGUUGGGAGAAAUUGUAAAAUACAGUAAUGUUAUACAACUACUGCAUAUAAAAAGCAACAAAUAUCUUACUGUCAACAAGAGAUUACCUGCUUUACUGGAGAAGAAUGCCAUGCGUGUGUCCUUGGAUGCUGCAGGAAAUGAAGGGUCUUGGUUUUAUAUUCAUCCGUUCUGGAAACUGAGAAGCGAGGGUGACAAUAUUGUUGUAGGAGAUAAAGUUGUUUUGAUGCCUGUGAAUGCAGGGCAGCCACUACAUGCCAGCAACAUAGAGCUUCUUGAUAACCCAGGGUGUAAAGAGGUGAAUGCUGUCAAUUGCAACACCAGCUGGAAAAUCACUUUAUUCAUGAAAUAUAGUUCCUAUCGAGAGGAUGUAUUAAAAGGAGGGGACGUUGUUAGAUUAUUUCAUGCGGAACAAGAGAAGUUUUUGACUUGUGAUGAAUAUGAGAAAAAACAGCACAUUUUCCUUCGUACGACCUUGCGCCAAUCAGCUACUUCUGCUACUAGUUCUAAAGCACUCUGGGAAAUAGAGGUGGUUCAUCAUGACCCAUGCCGUGGGGGUGCAGGACAGUGGAACAGCUUGUUCAGAUUUAAGCAUCUUGCAACUGGAAACUAUUUAGCUGCAGAGAUGGAGGGGUGCAGUUGUUUUUUAAUUGAUUGCGGUACAAGCAUGACUUUCACUGCCCAGCUUAAUCCUGAUUAUCGAGAUGCCCAAAAUGAAGGAAAAAAUGUGAGAGAUGGAGUCCCUCCAACUUCAAAGAAAAAACGCCAGGCAGGGGAGAAGAUCAUGUAUACUUUGGUUUCAGUCCCGCAUGGCAAUGACAUUGCAUCCCUUUUUGAACUAGAUGCCACAACUCUUCAGAGAGCUGACUGCCUGGUUCCAAGGAACUCAUAUGUUCGGUUAAGGCAUUUAUGCACCAACACAUGGGUAACCAGUACUAGUAUCCCCAUAGACACAGAUGAAGAGAGGCCUGUUAUGUUAAAGAUUGGAACCUGCCAAACCAAAGAAGAUAAAGAAGCGUUCGCAAUCGUGUCUGUUCCACUGUCUGAAGUUCGAGACUUAGACUUUGCCAAUGAUGCCAAUAAAGUACUAGCGACCACAGUUAAAAAGCUAGAAAACGGCACAAUAACUCAGAAUGAAAGGAGGUUUGUAACCAAAUUAUUGGAAGAUCUCAUAUUCUUUGUUGCUGAUGUGCCUAAUAAUGGACAAGAAGUUCUGGAUGUGGUUAUCACUAAGCCAAACCGAGAGCGUCAAAAAUUGAUGAGGGAACAAAACAUACUGGCACAGGUAUUUGGAAUUCUUAAAGCACCCUUUAAAGAGAAAGCAGGAGAAGGCUCGAUGCUGAGACUUGAAGAUCUGGGGGAUCAAAGAUAUGCACCCUACAAGUACAUGCUGCGGCUCUGUUACCGCGUCCUGAGACACUCGCAGCAGGAUUACCGGAAAAAUCAGGAAUAUAUUGCUAAGAAUUUCUGUGUCAUGCAGUCCCAGAUUGGCUAUGAUAUUUUGGCAGAAGAUACUAUCACAGCUUUGUUGCACAACAACAGAAAACUACUAGAGAAACAUAUCACAGCAAAAGAAAUAGAAACAUUUGUCAGUUUACUCAGGAGAAAUCGGGAGCCAAGGUUUUUGGAUUAUUUGUCAGAUCUGUGUGUGUCUAAUACCACUGCUAUCCCUGUAACUCAAGAACUCAUCUGUAAAUUUAUGUUGAGUCCAGGCAAUGCAGACAUUCUCAUUCAAACUAAGGUGGUCUCAAUGCAAGCAGACAACCCCAUGGAGAGCUCCAUCCUUUCAGAUGACAUUGAUGAUGAAGAAGUUUGGCUCUAUUGGAUUGACAGCAACAAGGAACCUCAUGGCAAAGCUAUCAGGCACCUUGCUCAAGAGGCAAAAGAAGGCACCAAAGCUGACUUAGAAGUUCUUACCUAUUACAGGUACCAGCUAAACCUCUUUGCAAGGAUGUGCUUGGAUCGCCAGUAUCUGGCCAUAAACCAGAUUUCUACACAGCUGUCUGUAGACCUGAUCCUGCGGUGUGUGUCGGAUGAGAGCCUGCCGUUCGACCUCCGAGCGUCCUUCUGUCGCCUCAUGCUCCACAUGCACGUUGACCGGGAUCCCCAGGAGUCCGUGGUGCCUGUUCGCUAUGCCAGGCUCUGGACAGAAAUCCCCACAAAGAUCACAAUUCAUGAAUAUGAUUCUAUAACAGACUCUUCCAGAAAUGAUAUGAAGAGGAAAUUUGCCCUGACAAUGGAAUUUGUUGAAGAAUAUUUGAAAGAAGUUGUAAACCAGCCCUUUCCUUUUGGGGAUAAAGAAAAAAAUAAACUGACAUUUGAGGUGGUCCACUUGGCUCGGAAUCUUAUAUACUUUGGAUUUUAUAGUUUCAGUGAGUUAUUAAGGCUAACAAGAACACUUCUGGCUAUUUUAGACAUUGUACAGGCCCCCAUGUCAUCAUACUUUGAAAGAUUAAGCAAAUUUCAAGAUGGAGGAAACAAUGUGAUGAGAACCAUUCAUGGGGUGGGAGAGAUGAUGACCCAGAUGGUACUCAGUAGAGGCUCCAUCUUCCCCAUGAGCGUGCCGGAUGUGCCACCCAGCAUCCACCCGAGCAAGCAAGGGAGCCCCACCGAGCACGAGGAUGUGACUGUGAUGGACACCAAGCUGAAGAUCAUUGAGAUUUUGCAGUUUAUCCUGAGUGUCAGACUGGAUUAUAGGAUCUCAUAUAUGCUGUCAAUAUAUAAGAAGGAGUUUGGAGAGGACAAUGACAAUGCGGAGACAUCUGCCAGUGGAUCUCCAGACACUUUACUACCAUCAGCUAUUGUUCCUGAUAUAGAUGAAAUUGCAGCUCAGGCAGAAACUAUGUUUGCGGGAAGAAAAGAAAAAAAUCCAGUUCAACUUGACGAUGAAGGAGGCAGGACGUUUUUACGGGUCCUCAUUCAUCUGAUCAUGCACGACUACCCGCCUUUGCUGUCUGGAGCCCUGCAGCUGUUGUUUAAGCACUUCAGCCAGAGGGCAGAGGUUUUACAGGCAUUUAAGCAGGUGCAAUUACUGGUGUCUAAUCAAGACGUAGAUAACUACAAGCAAAUCAAGGCAGAUCUAGACCAGCUUCGACUGACAGUAGAAAAGUCUGAGCUAUGGGUGGAGAAGAGCAGCAACUAUGAGAAUGGAGAAAUAGGGGAAAGUCAAGUGAAAGGUGGUGAAGAGCCAAUUGAGGAAUCAAACAUUUUAAGUCCAGUGCAGGAUGGAACAAAGAAACCUCAGAUUGACAGCAACAAGAGCAAUAACUACCGGAUUGUAAAGGAGAUUUUGAUCAGGCUAAGUAAACUCUGUGUGCAGAAUAAAAAGUGUCGGAAUCAACAUCAACGAUUACUGAAAAAUAUGGGGGCGCAUUCGGUGGUGUUGGAUCUUCUGCAGAUACCCUAUGAAAAGAAUGAUGAAAAGAUGAAUGAAGUAAUGAAUCUAGCCCAUACAUUUCUGCAGAAUUUCUGUCGAGGAAAUCCACAGAAUCAAGUUCUUCUUCAUAAACAUCUGAAUUUGUUUUUAACUCCAGGUCUCCUUGAAGCAGAAACCAUGCGGCACAUCUUCAUGAACAAUUACCAUCUGUGCAACGAAAUUAGCGAGAGAGUUGUACAACACUUUGUGCACUGCAUUGAGACACAUGGCCGCCACGUGGAGUACCUGAGGUUUUUGCAAACAAUUGUAAAAGCAGAUGGUAAAUAUGUGAAGAAAUGCCAGGAUAUGGUAAUGACAGAGUUGAUAAAUGGGGGUGAAGACGUGCUGAUAUUUUACAAUGAUAGAGCAUCAUUUCCAAUCCUUCUCCAUAUGAUGUGUUCAGAGAGAGACCGAGGGGAUGAGAGUGGCCCCUUAGCCUACCACAUCACCCUGGUGGAGUUGCUGGCAGCAUGCACAGAGGGGAAAAAUGUCUACACUGAAAUCAAGUGUAAUUCCCUUCUCCCGCUGGACGACAUAGUGAGGGUGGUGACCCAUGACGACUGCAUCCCUGAGGUUAAAAUUGCUUAUGUGAACUUUGUUAAUCACUGUUAUGUUGACACUGAAGUGGAAAUGAAAGAAAUCUAUACAAGUAACCACAUUUGGAAAUUAUUUGAGAACUUCUUGGUGGAUAUGGCAAGGGUUUGCAACACAACUACAGACAGGAAACAUGCAGACAUCUUUUUGGAAAAGUGUGUUACUGAGUCAAUAAUGAAUAUUGUGAGCGGCUUCUUUAAUUCUCCCUUUUCAGACAAUAGUACCAGCCUCCAGACACAUCAGCCAGUUUUUAUUCAGCUACUGCAAUCUGCCUUCAGAAUUUACAAUUGCACCUGGCCAAACCCAGCGCAGAAAGCCUCAGUGGAAUCCUGUAUCAGAACUUUGGCUGAAGUGGCAAAAAAUCGUGGAAUUGCCAUUCCAGUGGAUUUGGACAGCCAAGUUAAUACUCUUUUCAUGAAGAGCCAUUCAAAUAUGGUGCAGAGAGCAGCAAUGGGUUGGAGACUAUCAGCUCGCUCUGGGCCACGCUUUAAGGAAGCUCUUGGAGGGCCUGCUUGGGAUUACAGAAAUAUUAUUGAAAAGUUACAGGAUGUAGUGGCCUCCUUGGAGCACCAGUUCAGCCCAAUGAUGCAGGCUGAAUUCUCAGUGUUGGUUGAUGUAUUGUACAGUCCAGAACUGCUGUUCCCUGAGGGAAGCGAUGCAAGAAUAAGAUGUGGCGCUUUCAUGUCGAAGUUGAUUAAUCAUACAAAGAAACUAAUGGAGAAAGAAGAAAAACUGUGCAUUAAAAUUCUUCAGACAUUACGAGAAAUGUUAGAGAAGAAAGACAGCUUUGUGGAAGAGAUUAAGUGGUCCAAAGAAAAUGACUGCAUUUCUGUGCAUGCUGAUUGUCUUUGGCAUUCUGCGACCUGACUGCUUAACAGUGGAAGUGAUUUGGGGACAUGGAAAAAGCUGACAUUGUGAUCUUCUCACUCCUCCUUCUCUAGCCUGCUAAAGCUGUAAGUAAACAGGUGUGUGGUCAGGUCUUGUCAACAAAGUCUGUGGGAAGCAUCUUCUUUUCUUAUGGAAGCUACAUGUCUUCUUCUCAUCCUUUAUUAUGUUUAAUUCUGAAAUGGUUGGCAAAUACCACUAUGGCUUUUCUGUCACAUCUGGAAGAUGUGUAGUCUUAUUUUAUGAGAAGGAGUAAAAGGAUGGUGGGUGGAGUAGCCUGGUUGUAAUUAUAGUGUACGUUUAUUUGGAAAGACUAGCAUAUUAGUAUGCAGUGGCUAGAUUAAUUAAACUCAGCUGGCAUAAUUCAAUAUGGUUAGUUCCUGUAAAAGCAAACUGUCUUUAAACUCUUGAGGUUUGCUAUAAAGCUUAUGAUGAGAGCAACAUUUUGAAUGUCUCUUCCUCCCAUAUGAAUUACAAAGGCACUUAAAAGCUGUCCUUUUAAAAAUUUGUUUCCCUUCUCUCCCCACCCCCACCCCCCACCACACACACACACACACACACACACACACACACACACACACACACAAAACCCUUAUCUACUUGUUAACAAAAUAAAUUCUGGGAUCUUUUUUUAGGAAGAUGAGGGCUUUUUUAACUAACAUAUUUUGUGAACCAUAAUUUCCAUGAAGUUGUUUAUAAUUUUGAGUUUCUACACAUCAAGUAGUGUGAGGUAUCCAUGGAAACUGUCUAGCCUAUAUUCAGUGCACUGGACCGCCUUCCCACACAGGUCAAGACUCAAACAGUUCCAGAUACUAGCUUGAUUUAUUGUGCCCUAAACAUUAGACAGUUUUAAAAGGAAAUUGGCUCCUAAUUGACACAUACAAUUUCAUGUUUAAUUAGCAAUUUGAGCCUGUCUACAUUUUACUAACAGAUGUAACAUUCAAAACGUGCCAUUCUAAUAUAUCUGUUGCACAGAUGCACCUAAAUGCAGAACUUUAUGAAAUAGCAGCUCAGCUGCUUAGCAAAAAUUUGGACAGAACUGACAUUAUUUUCCUUAAGAGAUGUACUUUAAUGUUAUUUAAGGAGUGAUUUUCCUUAACCAAUCUAAUGGAUUUAUUUUAUAUUUUGGUAACAGCUUUAUUGAGAUAUUCACAUACUAUAAAAUUCACCCUACAAAAGUGUACAAUUUAGUGUUUUUUGGUUUAUUUACAGAUUUACAACCAAUACUGCUGUUUAAUUUUAGAACAUUUUCAUCACCCCUAAAAGAAACCCCAUGCCUCUUAGCAGUCACUCUUCAUUCUUCCCAGCCCCAGCCCUUGGCUAUCUAUUUUCUGUCUCUUUUUGUCUCUAUGAAUUUGCCUCUUCUGGACAUUUCAUAUAAAUGGAAUCAUACAAUAUGUGGUCUUUUGUGACUGCCUCCCUUCACUUGGCAUAAUGUUUUCAAGGCUCAUACAUGUUCUAGCAGGUGUCAGCACUUCAGUCCCAUUUUAUUGCCAAAUAAUAUUCUAUUAUGUGCAUAUACCACAUUGUGUUUAUCCAGUCAUCAUUUGGUGGACAUUUGGAUUGUCUCUACUAUUAUGGAUCAUGCCACAAUGAACAUUCUGUACAAGUUCUUGUGUGGACCUCUGUUUUAAUUUCUUUAGGGUAAAUACUUAGGAGUGGAAUUGCCGGAAUGUAUGGUAACUCUACGUUUAAUUUUUUGGAACUGCCAAGUGGCUGCACCAUUUUCUAUUCCCAUUAGCAGUGUAUGAGGGUCCCAAUUUCUCCACAUCCUCACCAACAUGUGUUAUUGUUCAGAUCACAAUGUCAGCUUUUUCCGUGUCCCCAGAUCACUUAUUUUAGCCAUUCUAGUGGGUGUGAGAUGGUAUCAAGGGGCAACUUUUUUUAAAAGGAGAGAAAUUUAAUAUUGUCCAUGGUUCAUAAAUUAGUUCAAUGUGUGUCUCUUACUUGUUUGCUUUUCCAUUACUCUUGAUUUGUAAGAUAAAUAUACCUCUCAUCUCUAUCAAUAUUGUCACUUUCCUUACUAAUUUUAAUGUAGGGGCCUAUGAUAUCAAAAUUUACAGUAGUGAAUUGGGCUACAUAUAGAAAAUGUAUCAUGAAAAAGGGAAAACACUGAAAUAACUGUUCGAUUGCAAAGGUUAAAUCUCUAAAUUUCUGUAUGUUUUCAUCUUACUUGACUUUAACUAGAAAACAGGUAUAAUAGUGAUGCCACAUACUGGGAAGCAAUGAGUAUUUGAUACAAUGCCAGAUUAAAAGGUGUACUUAUUUUUUCGUUCAAUAUAGUUCAUCAAUCAUAAAAUACCAUCAAUCAUAAAUAAGGCAUACCAUAAUUUUAUGUAUCCCUAAAAAUAAAUAAAUGCUGCCAAUUAAACUAAAGCACACCAUGGAUUUUAAAGUGACCUGUAAUUUAGAAAUGUUAAAACAUGCAGGAGAGAAAUGGGUGUGUUAGAAUCAAUGAAAUAAAGCAGAAAAGAGAUGUGCUUGCUCAGUGUUUUUUGAAGGCAACCCAGUCAUUUAUGCUUACCAACACCCAGGGGAGAUAGCAAGAAUCUUCAUACUUCAAAGACCUAAUUCAUUUUACAAAUAUGCAUCAAUAUCCAUGAGUACAAAAAUAGAUAUACGUAUAUAUUACACACAUACACACUGACAUACACACACACACACACACACACACACACACAGAGACAGAGAGAGAAGAGUAGAGAGAUAUUCAUUGACUCAUUCUUCCACACCUUAGGAGUAUUAGAUCAGCAUCAGCAACCUGUAGUUCACUGAAAUGAUUCUUCCUCUCUUCAAUUCACUGAUUCAGAAAAGCUGGUUUACCUCAAAUAAUGUUUAUUAAAUACUUUAAGCUUUCUUUUCAGCCUGAGAAUGUUUCAUCUUGUUUUUUCCAGAAGCUAAUUUCAAUAGGUGAAUCACAAACCUGUGAAAAUCCACAUUUAUAAUUCAGAGGCUAGCACCACAGUACUACCAAGCGGCUAUGCUUCCUUACCAGCAAAUGUGCUUUGCAUGUUAUUAAAAAUAAACGUUUACUUUCUUAGUGCCCCGGAUUAUAGUUACAGUUCUAAAUGCAUUAAAGUAGUGAAAUAUCUAUCACGGUGUAUGCCACAGGGAAUCAAACUGAUUUCCAAAAUAACAUUCAUAAGACCAUAAUAAGUCUAAUAAAGCCUUUCUUAAAAAGACCCUUUCUAAGGUAAGCAUUUGGUACUUGGCCCCUUUAAUUAGCUCAGGCAUCUCUAGGUUUGUUUGAACUGAGACCUCAUUUUCUUUUAGUAAUAAUUGUGUUACUGCUUUGAAAUGUUGAUGAAAAUUUAAAGGAUUUCUAUUUUUCAUUAGUUCUAAAUCAUUGUCUCAUAGUUUUCUCUCUGCAAAAUUCUUUGAAAAUUGUGGUUUACAUGUAGAACACAAUUAGGAGCUCAUGGGAGCAGAUAAUUGCUCAUAUUAAAGUAGGCCAAAUAUGUGGCCUCCUGGACAAAUAGAUGCAAGAAAUGAUUAAGAUUAGAUUUAUAUAAUUUUUAAUGUAGCAAUGAACACUAAAGAAAUGAAAUGAUUUAUUUCAUGAGGAAAAAUGAGGUAAAAGAAUUAUCUUUAUCUUCUAUUAUAAAUUAUGACACAUUCAAACAUAUUUUAAAAGAGAAUAGUGAAUUUGUAUCUCUUCAAAUUGACAUAUUCACAUAAUAUUAGGAAUUAUGUUGCUGAGUCAGAUCCUUGUAUGACGUGCAGCCUUAAGGUGGUUUCUUUGUUUUUUAGUAAAAUACGAAAAUCCUAUUGCAGUAGACAUAUUGUAGCAGGGGGAUAACCUGGACUGGACUUUUGGGAUAUUAGUGUGUUCUCUUGCAUUAGGCUACAUUUGUGAUCAUUAAUUAGUAUUUUACCUUCUAAUCUUUCAGGCUAAAUAUUGAAAUUGUCUGUCUUUUAAGUUUUAUAACAUUUUGCUUGCUGGAUUUCAACACAAUUUCCUUCUUUCAGCCGACCAUAGGUAAUGAGUUUUGUGUGCUAAUUUUUUUUUUUUUUUUUUUUUUUUGAGACAGGAUUCCUACUCCCAGGCUGGACAGGGUCUCCCAGGCUGGAGUGCAGUGUGCAAUCAUGCCUCACUGCAGCCUUGAUUUCCCAGGCUCAAGCGAUCCUCCCACCUCAGCCUCCUAGUAGUUGGGACCACAGGCGUAUGUCACCACACCCAGAUUAUUUUCCUAUUUUUAUUAGAGAUGAAGUCUUGCUAAGUUUCCCAGGCCAGUCGUAAACUCCUGAGCUCAAGUGAUCCUCCUGCCUGGGCCUCCUGAGUAACUGGGACCAUAGGUGUAUGUUAUCACACCAGGCUAAUUUUUUUUUUUUUAAUUUGGUAGAGAAGAGGUCUCCCUAUAUUGCCUAGGCUGGUCUUGAACUCCUGGGCUCAAGAAAUCCUUCUGCCUUGGCCUCCUAAAGUGCUGGGAUUACAGGCAUGAGCCAGUAAUACAAUGUAAUAUUUACAUAUUAAGUAUUUUUAGUACAAGGCUGGGCAUCUUGUAUUUUUAGUACUAUGCUAAAUAUUUGAAUAUUUUUAGUACAAGGCUGAGUGCCUUGUAGUUUUAGUAUUAAUACAAGGCACCCAGCCUUGUACUAAAAAUAUGUAAUAUGCAAGUAACAUUGAAUAAAUCUCAAAUGUUUUCCAAAGUUAUCAGACAUGAUAUACAACAAAUAUCAGCCAUCCUUGAAUAGGUUGGCACUCAGCAUCAAAUUUUGUUGAUAAAUUGAGUGAUCUCUCAUUCAAAAUCAUUGAUUCAUACAUUCAGUCAAAAAUAUUUAUUGAGUACUUAGUUUGCUAGCUUUGGGGCUAGGUGUUGGAAUCAAUGGUCAGCCAAAAAGGAAAAAAAGAAAGGUAUAGUUCCUGUCCUCAUGGUACUUAUAAUCUAAUAGAGGGUGAUAGAAAUCAUUGAAAGAUUGGUAUAAAUAAAUAUACAGCUAAAGCACAUGGUGAUAUACAUGCUAUUAUAAGAGGACUUAAUGAGAAUUGACUUGGUGCGGUUAGAGAGGAUGACUCUGAGGAAGAUAUGGUUGAGCUGAGAUCUAAAGGUUAAGUAGGAAUUAAGUAAAGCCAGGAGGACUCAGGGUCGGGGGACAGAAAGCAUGGCUGGUGAAAGAGAACAUCAUCUGUUAAUGUCUUGAAGCAGAAGGGAGCAUGAUAAGACACUAAGAAGCUGUGUGGCAGAAGGAAGAUGUGGAUUGUUCAGAAGACAAUGAGACAGUGGCUCAAAUCUGUAGGUGUUGCAUUGUGUAUCAUCCCCUAAAGUAAUGCUAUGGAUUUUAGCCAGGAUUCAAAGAGAGCUGGAAAGUAACAGAACAUCCUAUGUAGGAAGCUGUCAUCAUGAUGUCUAAUAGUUCUUGAGCAUUUUCUUUUCCUAUAAUAUUGAAUUUUUAUGAAGAAAUAUAUACAACAUAAAUUUUAGCUAUAAAGCAUUAAAUAUAAUAAAGACUCAUGACCUCAGCCAAAUGAAGAAUGAGAACAUUACCUGUAACUUGUGUCUACAUAUGUGUUCUGGCCUCCCCUUCCAGAGGUAGCUCACGUUUUGAAUACCAUACUGCAUAUCUUCUAGGACUUCCCUUUUUUUCCCUGUCAUCAUUCUAUUUCUAACAUUCAUGAAAGUAGUUGUGUGUUACGGUGAGGCUCUGUUUAAUCCAUGUUUACUACUCUAUAAUAUUCCAGUUUGGGAAUAUUCUAUAAUUUAUUUGUCAAUUUUCCUGUCACUUGUUAUUUGGGUUGAUUCCAGGUGAUGUUUUGCUUGUUGUUUGUUUUGCUAUUGCUAUCAUGCAGAUAUAAAUGUCUAGGAUGGGAUACUAUUUGUUUCCUUGAGCAUGUUUCCCCUGGGAGUGAAAUUGGUGGCUGAGAGCAUACAUUGAUGUGAUUUCCAAAGUAGUUGUACCAAUUUGCAUCCCACAUUCUCUUGAUCCAUGUCCUCUUCAACACUUGAUUUUGUAAGACUUCUUAAUUUUUGUCAAUUUAUUGGGUAUAAAAUGGUGUCUCCACCAUUUUAUUAGCAUUUCUUUGAUUACCAAUGAAGGUGAGCAUUUUUUUUCAUGUUUAUUGGCUGUAUGUGUUUCUUAUAUGAAAUGCCAGUUCAGUUCUUCUGUCAGCUUUUCUACAAGAUUCUUAAUGAUUUAUAAACACUCUUUGUAUAGUCAUGUAUUCUGAAUACCAGUCAUCUGUUGUUUUGCAAGCCUCUGAAUGUUAAGUGAGCAAUGACUUAGAGGGGCAUCCUGUGGAUAUGGAGAGACAUAUGGAUAUGUGUUAGGAAGCACAGCCUUUCCACUAAUGAACAAUUGUUGCUGAUAAUAACUUUAUAAAUAUACUUAAUACAUUUCUUGUGUUAAAACUAAAUAGGAGGGAAAAUAGCUCUUUUCCCACAGAACAUGGAAUAUUGGUUUUCCAUUUAACACUACUUCAAGGAAAGGCUGUCUAAAUUAUCUUCUGAAGAAUUCUGCUUUGUACAUGUAAUAGGGGUGAUUGAAACCUAUCCACAAGUAAGUGUUAUUUUUAAGAAAUUGUAGCAUACUGAUCAAAUUGGCUUCAAAGUAGUCUUUCACAAAAUGAAUGCUGUUUUUCAUUUGCCUUCUCUUGAAAAAUUAUAGAAGGUUGGAGCUGGAUAUUGAUGUCAGCUGUGAAAACCAUGGCUGUCUUGUGGCACUGGGCAUUGUAAUGUCCUCUUUAUGUCAUCAAUUGUACAAGUCUUCCCCAGAUUGAAACUUAUUAAUGCUUUCCUUUAAACAUAAAAUAAAAUAUUACAGUAGCUGUUUAUUCAGUACUUGCUAUGGGCCAAGAACAUAAAGCUUCUCCUAUUUAAUUUCCUAAUCCUUAAAUAGCCUUGCAGUGUAAAUAUUAUUAUCCACAGAUGGGGAAACUGAGCCUUGGGGCAGUUAAUUAAAAUUCUUUAGAUCACAAAGCCAAUAAGUGGAAGAACCCAGACUCAAACCAAUCACAUUACUCUCUGAGACAUCAUUUCCACUAAGGUCCACUAACGUGCAUUGUCAUUGCCAAUGCCGGGAGCAUUCAUAAACUGAACUUCUUAUGUAUUAAAGUGUGUAUAGAUAUUAUCUCAUUUAAUUCUCAAGGUUUCCCUUUGGAGUUGUGCCAUGUAGAACUCCUCUAUUCCAUGGAUUCCAUAGACUGUCCUAUCUGAGGAACUUCUAAAUGUAUUCUGAAUUUAUUAAAAUUUAGCUUCAUACAUAUUUUGUCAAAUAUUGCAUUGAUUGAUAAGUAAUACCAGUGCCAGUUUUCUUCCUCUCUUUUAAGAAUAAUCUAUUUCUAGUAUUUUGGGGAAAAAUAAUGAGGUCUUUGUCUCUCACUUAAUCCGUGUGUGUGUGUGUGUGUGUGUGUGUGUGUUGGUGGGGGGCAGUGGGUCUUCUACCCCAUUGUUUCCUUGCCAGCUCUUCGGAGCCAUGCACUCGUCUCACUGCCCUGUGAACCAGCCACACUCUCUUGUUUGUGGGUCAGGAGGUCACAGCUUGAAGAUCAAGGACUGCACUACUGUUGAGAAUGCAAGAAACUCCAUAGAAACAGGAAGGCCAAUAUAGAGCAGGAUAGUGCUGGUGAUAUGUCCCCGUAUGUAUUGUUCCUCAUCUCCUGUGACACCACCUUCCAAAGUUGUGCCUGUCUUCACUAAAUGAUUAUGGAAAUAUAACAGACAUCACAGAAUCUGGGGAUAGAACUUUAAAACAGCAAACUAGUUAUGACUUUCCCCAUUGUCUAGGAGGAAGACCUUUCUCCCACUGAAGUUCAUAUUGCUAUUCAGAUCAGUGUCAGUCUUCUCAUUUAUUUAAAUCUCAUUCCAUCUCCUGCUCUUUCCUCUUGUACUCUCUGGGAUGCACUGUAAGCUGAGUCCAUUACUGAGUUACAUACUUUGCCUUACCCCCCACUCAGCAACAUAGUCUUUGCAGAAGCUUUGAAAUUACCUCUUGAAGUUCCAUUUUCCCCAGUCUUUGGUGAGCAUGCACACGCCUGCACUGACAGCACUGAUUUCAUUCUUUUCAGUAACAAACAGUACUCUAGUAGGUUUUUAUACUGUGUACCAGGGACUAUGGGCUUCACUUUAAUGAUUGUGUGCCACUGUCUUUGAGUGUGAUUUUAUGAGGCACUGAUUUAUGUUAUGUGAAUACAGUCAUUUUCCUUCAUUAAGGAGAUGGUAUCUAAAGCUUGUCUGCUCACUUCUUGCUUACUUACCCUCCUCUCAGCUUAAAGUCAGAAGACUGCUUAUUCUGAAAACUAAACAAUUACAAGCAGUAAAAUCCAUUCUUAAGUCCUAUUGGUGAGGGAUUGCAUAAGUUCUCAAACUCUGAAUUUCAGCAAACCCUGUAUUUAAAAUGGUUGAGGUAGAAGGGUCUGUUGGGUUUCAUGUUAGUUAGUAUGCUUCCUGGAAUUCAAAUACUGGGAGGUUUUAAUUAAUGCCCCAAGGAAAACAAAUACAGUUUGCUUUAUUCCUUGCUAUCUAUGGAGUAUAGAAUCAUCUCCUAACAAAACCUUCUCAGCAACCCUGUUUGUCUUGAGGCUAGGAUAUUUGAUAAACUCAGAGUGGUUAUUGAAGUCACUCUUUCAUUCAGCAGCAGCAUCAAAUAUUUAAACCUCAUCAUUUACUGUUUAAACAUUUAAUUUUCACCAAUGGAAUCAAAUGGUCUGGUGAGGAUUAUUUAUAUUGGAAAACAGUGCCAUAUGUUUCAACUCCACAUAUCUGAAAAUUCUUUCAGCAUAUGCUGCAGAAUUGCUUUUUGCAUCCACUUUUCUACUUCCUGACACAUGGUAGAAAUGUAAUAAAUGUCUUUACAAUCAAUAAAAACAAGGAAAGAAGAAAUUUGGAAGUAGGUUGCCAUUAUGGUGAAUGAAUAUUUGGAUCUAACAUUUUCCACAGUCUUGUUUUUUCACAAGGCUCUUUACUAGAAUCAUUGAGACAUCAUAUAUUUUUCAAGAUUGUAAUGAGUAUGUCAUUGUGUUGAUGAGAAGAGCAUCUUCUGAGUGCACAUAACUAGUCCUGUUGAAAUUUGUGUUUCCUGUCUUAAGAAAGCUAGGCAAAGGCAACAGGGAGAGAAAUUGACUUACAACUUCUUGGACAGGGAGACUAAGAUGUUCAAAUGAUUAAACAGCUAGAUUAUAGGAGAUUGACCAUAUUCUCCCGAAGGAGUUAUCUGAAAAUAUAGUUGAUUAUAACGAUGGACAGAAUAUCACUCCACAAAGAUACAGUUGUUACAUUAAUGUAUUGAAAUGAGAAAUGUACCUUUUUACCCCUGGCAAUUCAAAUGAGGAAAAAUACCUAAUCAGACGUAUUGUUACUAAGCCAAAAGGUUACAGAAACACAAAUUAUGCUAAUACCAAGUUUAAUGUUAAAAUGGGACUAUGGGGAGACUAACAGGUACCUAUCAUCACCUCCUUGUAGAUCUUGUCUCAGCUGAUUGGUAGCUUAUCAUGAAUCUUUGAGGAUAAGUCUUAAAUUGGGCAUCCUUAGUUUGCAGUUUUUAUUACAUUUUGAAUUUCUAGUUGAGGACUUAGUUUUCUAGGAUGCUGGUUGUGUUUUUUCAUGAUAUCUUGAUUAUAUUUUACAUAAUGAAAAAAUAUUACUUUAGUAAAUUGUUUUUCUAAGGGGAUGGGAAUGAAUGUGGGUAGCUAUACCUCAAAUAUCACACAUCCUUGAAGUCUUCAUUCCUAAGGCUAUUAACUCCCCAUUAAGGCAAACAGAGUUGUGCUUUCUCAAAAAUGAAACAAAAUUUUAGUCCUUUCUAGGAUGCAUAAAUUUGAUUAUCCUUUCUAUCCAUGAAAGGCAAUGAUUUCUGAACUUUUUAAUUUUUGAUGCAUUGGACUCGGUGUAACAGGGAGUGGGUGGGAAAAACCCAAUCCUCCCAGAUAUUCACAAACCAUCAGCAGGACUUCUCUGGCCACAAAAGAUGUCUUUUUAUGGAGAUAUUUUGUUGUAAUUUCAGAAGGUGGUUGUUAGUUUUCUUGGCUACAUUACAUUUAGCACAUCUGGGAUGUGUUCACAUGAAGACAUUGGCUAAAAGUAGUGUCUUGUGGCCUGGAAUUGACUCUGAUAUUGAAAAGGCUGUAAAGGACAUUCCUUGCUUGUCCUCACUCAGCAAAGAGACCUUCCAUGGGAGGUGCAUCAGGAAUGCAUUUUGGAUUUGAAGAACCAGCACAGAAGUCAAACUUCUCAACUGUGGUGAAAUUCUUUUCAUAAUGGCCUAAUGUGCUUUUAGUUCUUCCCUCAUUUCUGCCAUGGCAAUUAUAGCUCUGAGACAAUUAUUUGCAACCCUGGCACCAGAAUUUCUGACAAUGAUUCUGCAGUUACUUUUGAAUUAAAGUAAUUUGGGGAAAUGACUCACAUUUAAGCUACCACCACUGCACAGAUAGUGCAAACUAUCAAGAAUGCCCCAAAAGCAAAUUGGGACACAGUACAUGUCUCUCACCGCUUAAGUCAGAACUGGAUAGUUGACAAGAGAAGUCAGUUUCUGCUGAACUUGUGAUGUAGCAAUAUCUGAAUUUUUUUAUUCUUAAAUGAAGAUUACUAAGACAUAACAGAAUCUUGUUCUGUUUAUACCUAUUCAUUAAUCAUUUUUAGCACCAGAGUUUGUCUUAGCACAAAACUCUGAAGUUUGAACCAAGACAGAAUUUGUUCCAACUUUAGUUGAAGUUGUAAGGGUACAUUUUAUAUAGUGAAGUAUAUUCAUGCUUUAGGGUGACUUUGCCAUGUUAGCUAAUAAGUAUAUAAUUCUAAGGACUGAUUAAUAGUUAAAAAGCUAGGAUUUAGGGGCAGUUUAUCAUUUAUUAUUUUUCACAUUUUCUUAAUAUACUGGAAAUUUAUUUCACUUUUGUGGGAAGGUUUGGUAUAACAUAAGAAAGUGUCUGCAAAAGCACUUUGCAAGUUGUAGACUGUUCCCAUGAUCUGGAUAAUAUUAAUACUAGCAGGGAUAACAUCAACAAUGUACAACUUUUAUAGCACUUACUAUGUGUUUGGAACUGUUCCAAGUACUUUCAGUAAAUUUUAACUAUUUAAUUAUCACAGAAAUCCUCUGAGAGUAGAUAUUAACAAUUUCAUUUGACAAUUGAGGGACUGAGGCCCAGAGUGAUGAAGUAACUUGUUUAAGAUCCCCAGUUAGUAUAUGGCAUAGAGGGGAUUUAAACCCAGGCAGAGUGGCUUCAGAGUUGACAACAGAAAAAUAGGAAGCCCCUGCCUUUUCUAUGGCAGUCUGAAUAUUACAUGGUGAGGAAAUAGAUGCUUCUAAUGGGGCUAUAAUUGAAUAAGAAGAGUGUUACUCGUUUGAUUUUGAUGUCUAUGAAUCUGAUAGGCACUGUGAUUAUAUCUGCCGAAGAGAAUUUAAAAAUAAUCACAAAUAUGAUGCUUAUUUUUAUUUGGUGUGACAUAAUUCUACUCUUUGGUUGGUUUUCAAUAGUUUCAUUAUUCUAGCAGUAUAAACGGCAUUUUAAAAAGUAAAUGGUAAAAAAGUUUUCUAUUUCAUCUUUAAAAAAAUUUAUUUGUUUAUCUGUUGGUUGGGUUCUUGUAGCAGUGUGAUAAAUGGUGUGAUUAAAAGAUUCUUCCAGGGCCAGGUUCAUGUCUGUAAUCCCAGAACUUUGGGAGGCCAAGGUGAGAGGGUUGCUUGAGGCCAGGAGUGUGAGGUUGCAAUGAGCUAUGAUUGUGCCACUGUACUCCAGCCUGGGCAACACAACAAGACCCUAUCUCUAAAUAAUAAUAGAAAUAAUAAUACAUAAAAGGUUCUUGCAGAGACUAAAAGGGGAGCUAGUUCUCAAGGGUUCAGUCCUCUUCACAAUAGGUUCCCUUUCAGACAGUGAUGCUGACUUGUGCAAUUUCAAGAAAAAGUCCUGGAUUUUCACACUGUCAGCUUUAGUUAUUACAGGUGGGCCAACUGUCUUCUACAGGGUUAGAGUGAGUGGUCUGUAGAGGUGAGAUCCAUGAAUAGUACAACAAACUGAGCUACUCUUUAAAAAAAUGAGUGCUUCAGUUAAUGUGACCUCAUAUUUUUCUCCCCAACUUAUAACUUCAACCCUGUAGUUUAUGGGUCUAAAAGAUUUUUCAUAGCAUCUCCUUCUACUAUAAUGAGAGUCGCAGUAAUUACCCAAAGGCGUUGACUCCAAAGAAAAGCUUUGUUUUGUUUUUCCUUUCCUUUUGGAAGAAAUUUUCUUUGGCCAGGUGAAUUUAAUUCAACUCAAAGGACUUUCUCUUAAAAAAAGAAACAGUAAGGACGAUUUUCAUGUCUUAUGUUUCUUCUAGGUGCUGCACUUAAGUGUUAUCAGGAAUAGUAAAUAGUAGAGUUGUAUUCCUUGGUAGAAUAAGCUGUUAUACUUCACUGUUUCUUUUGAGACUAGUCACCACCUUUACUUACUACACCCCAUUAUGAAGAGGUCUUAAAGAAAGAAAACAUGAAAUAGGAAGCAAUAAUAACUGUCUAUGUUCUAAGAAUUUAAGUACCAAUAAAUAAAAGUUGUUACAAGGAUAAACAAACUCCAGACACUCUGAGUGUCUAUUAGAAUUCUUGGCACUGACCGGGCACGGUGGCUCAUGCCUGUAAUCCCAGCACUUUGGGAGGCUGAGGCCGGCAGAUUGCCUGAGGUCAGGAGUUCGAGACCAGCUCUGGCCAACAUGGUGAAAUCCAGUCUGUACUAAAAAUACAAAAAACAAAACAAAACAAACAAAAAAAAUUAGCCAGGCGUGGUGGUGUGUGCCUGUAAUCCCAGCUACUCGGGAGGCUGAGGCAGGGGAAUUGCUUGAACCAGGGAGGUGGAGGUUGCAGUGAGCUGAGAUUGUACCACUGCACUCCAGCCUGGGCAACAGAGUGAGACUCCGUUUCAAAAAAAAAAAAAAA